GUUUCCGGCUCCGGUGUCAUGGCCGGCUCCUACCCUGAAGGUGCACCUGCAAUCCUCGCCGAUAAGAGGCAGCAGUUCGGAAGCCGGUUCCUGAGCGAUCCGGCGCGCGUCUUCCACCACAAUGCCUGGGACAAUGUGGAGUGGUCGGAAGAGCAAGCCGCGGCGGCGGAGAGAAAAGUCCAGGAGAACAGUAUCCAGCGGGUGUGCCAGGAGAAACAAGUUGAUUAUGAGAUCAAUGCCCACAAAUACUGGAAUGACUUCUACAAAAUCCACGAAAAUGGGUUUUUCAAGGAUAGACAUUGGCUUUUUACCGAAUUCCCUGAGCUGGCACCUAGCCAAAAUCAAAAUCAUUUGAAGGAUUGGUUCUUGGAGAACAAGAGUGAAGUAUGUGAAUGUAGAAACAAUGAGGAUGGACCUGGUUUAAUAAUGGAAGAACAGCACAAGUGUUCUUCGAAGAGCCUUGAACAUAAAACACAGACACCUCCUGUGGAGGAGAAUGUAACUCAGAAAAUUAGUGACCUGGAAAUUUGUGCUGAUGAGUUUCCUGGAUCCUCAGCCACCUACCGAAUACUGGAGGUUGGCUGUGGUGUGGGAAACACAGUCUUUCCAAUUUUACAAACGAACAAUGACCCAGGACUCUUUGUUUAUUGCUGUGAUUUUUCUUCCACAGCUAUAGAACUGGUCCAGACAAAUUCAGAAUAUGAUCCUUCUCGGUGUUUUGCCUUUGUUCACGACCUGUGUGAUGAAGAGAAGAGUUACCCAGUGCCCAAGGGCAGUCUUGAUAUUAUCAUUCUCAUAUUUGUUCUUUCAGCAGUUGUUCCAGACAAGAUGCAGAAGGCUAUCAACAGGCUGAGCAGGCUUCUGAAACCUGGGGGGAUGGUACUUCUGCGAGAUUACGGCCGCUAUGACAUGGCUCAGCUUCGGUUUAAAAAAGGUCAGUGUCUAUCUGGAAAUUUCUAUGUGAGAGGUGAUGGAACCAGAGUUUACUUCUUCACACAAGAGGAACUGGACACGCUUUUCACCACUGCUGGACUGGAAAAAGUUCAGAAUCUGGUGGACCGCCGACUGCAGGUGAACCGAGGGAAGCAACUGACAAUGUACCGGGUUUGGAUUCAGUGCAAAUACUGCAAGCCCCUUCUGUCCAGCACCAGCUAAGAGGCACCUGCUGCCAACACGAUGCAAGCCCGUUGUGUUUCCGAGCUUUUUUAAAAAAAAAUUUGUAGCACCGGGCAUGGUGCAUGCCUGUAAUCCCAGCCACUCAGGAGGCUGAGGCAGGGAGGAUCCAUUGAGCCCAGGAGUCCAGCCUGGGCAAAAUAGCGAGAGACCCUGAAUCUGAAAGUAAUGAUAAAAUAAAAAGAAUAUAAAUGAGGUCUCGUUGAUGCUGGACAAUUCAAGAAUUCAGACUUGAACCUUAAACCUAGGAAAAGUUACUUUGUAUCAGGAUUCUAACAAUUAUGCUUCAUAUUUGUGAAGUCCUUUAAAACAUAAUUUUCUCAAGUUCUUUCUUUGAGACCUCAAUCUGUCUUAGCAUUUUGUAACUAAUAACUGAAAUUUUAUUCAAAGGAAUUGUAAACCUUAAACCACCAUUUAUUUCCAUGUGAAAAAGUGUUAUAUAUGACAAGUGUUUUUUGAUUGUAAUUGCGUUAAAUCUUUUGAGAGUGUAAAUGCCGGGCUAGGCAAUUGCAGUUAAUACAUACAGGGGUUAGUGAAGGGCUUAUUAAGUUGUAGGGGAAGCAAGCUGGGAAGAAUCAGAUCAGAUAUUUUCCUGACAAGAAAAAAAUGACCCUGUAGACAGCAUCAAAAUGUGGUGUUCUUGUUAAGUAAUUGAUCGUGGUCUUUGCUUUAAUCUUAGUUCCGCCAGGCACGGUGGCUCACACCUGUAAUCCCAGCACUUUGGGAGGCCGAGGCGGGCAGAUCACCUGAGGUCAGGAGUUCGAGACCAGCGUGGCCAACAUGGUGAAACCCCGUCUCUACUAAAGAUAAAAAAAUUAGCUGGGUGUGUUGGUGGGUGCCUGUAAUCCAGCUACUCGGGAGGCUGAGGCAGGAGAAUCACUUGAACCCAGGAGGCAGAGGUUGCAGUGAGCUGAGAUUGCGCCACUGUACUCCAGCCUGGGCAACAAAGCAAGACUCUGUCUCAAAAAAAUAAAAAUAAAAAAAAUCUUAGUUCCAUGGAAUUUUAAGCACUGUUCCCCCUCUAACCUAUGUCUAAAGAAUUAAAAGAAUUUGGCUGGGUGCGGUAGCUCAUGCCUGUAAUCCCAACACUUUGGGAGGCUGAGGCAGGUGGAUCACGAGGUCAGGAGAUCGAGACCAUCCUGGCUAACACGGUGAAACCUCGUCUCCACUAAAAAUACCAAAAAAAAUAGCUGGGCAUGGUGGCAUGCGCCUGUAGUCCCCUGUAGUCCCAGCUACUCGGGAGGCUAAGGCAGGAGAAUCGUUUGAACCUGGGAGGCAGAGGUUGCAGUGAGCCGAGAUCAUGUCACUGCAUUCCAGCCUGGGCAACAGAGGAAGACUCUGUCUCAAAAAAAUAAAAGAAAAGAAUUUUCACUUUUUGCAAAAUUAUCUUUUUUUACUGCACCCUUAAGUGUUUGACACAAAAGGAAUUGAGAGAACUUCUUAAUUUUAACCACAUCAUCACUUCACUUCUGAAUGUGAUCACUGUCAGUGUUAGAUGCUUUUUUUUUUUUUUUUUAGGAGACAGGGCUCUCACUUUGUUGCCCAGGCUGGAGUUCAGUGGUGCAAUGAUAGCUCAUUAUCACCUCGAACUUCUGGCUUGAGCCAUCGCUCCACCUCAGCCUCCUGAGUAGCUAGGACUGCAGGUGGGCACCAUCAUGCCUAGCUAAUUGUUAGAUCCUUUUUUUUUAUGUUCUGCAUUUUUUCAAUUAUUUUUACAUAUUUCUGUCUUGAUCCAUGCAGUUAUAGGAUAUAUCCUUAAUUUUAGAAAGUAAGGACUUUUCGACCAGGCAUGGCGGCUCACGCCUAUAAUCCCAGCACUUUGGGAGGCUGAGGUGGGCAGAUCACUUGAGGUCAGGAGUUCCAGUCCAGCCCGGCUAACAUAGUGAAACCCCGUCUCCACUAAAAAAUAAAAAAUCAGCCCGGCAUGGUUGUGGGCGCCUGUAAUCCCAGCUACUCAGGAGGCUGAGGUAGGAGAAUUGCUUGAACCUGGGAGGCGGAGGUUGCAGUGAGCUGAGAUGGUGCCAUUGCACUCCAGCCUGGGCGACAAGAGCGAAACUGCAUCUCAAAAACAAAGAUGCCUAGCUUUCACCUUGUUGAUGUUUUUCUAAAUUUUGGAAUAAUAAAUUUAUAUAGGAAUACUGCAAGAAUAGUCCAUUUUUUUCUGAUGUCCCAACAUCAGCAAAUAUAUUACCAAAUAUAUCCAUCACAAGUAGGAAUACAUGGAAACAUUAAUGCCAGCCACUAACCAUUCAUGUUUACCCAGUAGUCCCAAUAAUAGCUUUGUCACACAAAAACAUGAUUAUGUUGGCUGGGCACAGUGGCUCCUGUAAUCUUAGCAUUUUGGGAGCCCAAGGCAGGAGGAUGACUUGAGGCCAGGAGUUCAAGACCAGGCUGGGUAAUGUAGCAAGACCCUGACUUUUUUUUUUUUUUUUUUUGAGAUGGAGUUUCGCUCUUGUUGCCCAGGCUGGAGUACAAUGGCACGAUCUCGGCUCACUGCAAUCUCCACCUCCCAAGUUUAAGUGAUUCUCCUGCCUCAGCCUCCCAAGUAGCUGGAAUUACAGGCAUGCAGCACCAUUCCCAGCUAAAUUUUUUGUAUUUUUAGUAGAGACAAGGUUUCUCCAUGUUGGUCAGGCUGAUCUCGAACUCCCGACCUCAGGUGAUCUGCCCGCCUCAGCCUCCCAAAGUGCUGGGAUUACAGGCGUGAGCCACCACGCCCGGCCAAGACCCUGACUUUUUAAAAAAUGUUAAACAUAGGCCGGGUGCAGUGGCUCACGCCUGUAAUCCCAGCACUUUGGGAGGCCGAGGUGGGCGGAUCAUUUGAGGUCAGGAGUUCGAGACCAGCCUGGCCAACUUAAUGAAACCCCAUCUCUGCUAACAAUACAGACCAGGCAUGGUGGCUCACACCUGUAAUCCCAGCACUUUGAGAGACCGAGGCAGGUGGAUCACCUGAGGUCGGGAGUUCGAGACCAGCCUGACCAACAUGGAGAAACCCCGUCUCUACUAAAAAUACAAAAUAGCCAGGUGUGAUGGCGCAUGCCUGUAACCCCAUCUACUUGGAAGGCUGAGGCAGGAGAAUCACUUGAAUCUGGGAGGCAGAGGUUGCAGUGAGCCGAGAUGGCGCCAUUGCACUCCAGCCUGGGCAACAAGAGUGAAACUCCGUCUCAAAAAAAAAAAAAAAAAAAAAUUAGCUGGGCAUGGUGGUGGGCGCCUGUAAUCCCAGCUAUCUGGGAGGCUGAGUCUAGAGAAUCAUUUGAACCUGGGAGGCGGAGGUUGCAGUGAGCCGAGAUCGCACCAUUGCACUCCAGCCUGGGCAACAGUGAGACUCCGUCUCAAAAUAAAAAAACAAAAAAAAUGUAAAAAAUAAAUAAUUGUAUUGAAUUUAUUAGUUGUGUCUCAGUCUCCUUCAGUCUACAGUUUAGGCUUGCUUUUGCACCUUUGCAUUUUAAGGUAAGAGGCUAUUGUGUAAACUCGAAUUGGGUUUGUUGGUGUUUCUUCAUGAUUUGGUUCAGGCUCUGCAUUUUGGGCAGGAAUAUUCAGAGGUGAUGCUGUGUUCCUCCCAUAGGAUCGUAUCAGGCGACACAUGAUUAUGAAUUUCCCCAUUAUUGGUGAUGUCACUUAGUUGUGUUGUCUGCCAGGUUCUGCCACUGUAAAGUUAAUAAGUAUUUUGUAGGGAAGUGCUUUGAGACUAAAUAUCCUGUUCCUCAUCAAACUUCUACCCCCUAGUUUCAGUAUCUAUUGCUGUUUUUUGUCUGAAUAACUAUGAUAGUUGCCAAAUAGUGGUUUCUGAUCCUUCCAUUCCUUCUACACUGAUUGGUUGGUAUUUUGUACAGAAAAGCUUUCUCAUAUCUGAUUUACUUGUCUCAAUAUGGACCCAUGGGUAUUUGAGUUUCUUGUGGGGUUAUUUGUUGUUGUUUUUGAGACAGGCUCACCCAGGCUGGAGUGCAGCAGCACGAUCACUGCUUACUGCUUACUGCAGCCUCGACCUCCCAUGCUCAAGUGAUUCUCCCACCCCAGCCUCCCAAGUAGAUGGGACUACAGGCAUGUGCCACCAAGCCUAAUUUUUGUAUUUUUUGUAGAGACAGGGUUUCACCAUGUGUCCCAGGCUGGUCUUGAGCUCCUGAGCUCAAGCAAUCCUCCCACCUCGGCCUCCCAAAGUGCUGGGAUGAGCCACCGUGACUGGCCCCACUUAAUGGGUUUUCAGAGGUGGGAGCAAAGAAUGAAGGGAGGAAGAGAGCUCCCAUCUUUUCCAUUACCGUAUUUACUUAAAACUGGAAAAAACUGAAUCACUGGGAUGGUAUUUCAUUUAUCUUUUGAAAUGAAGAAUAGAUACAUUAAUUUAAAUGAUUCUCUAAAGACUGUCCUUCAGCAUCCCUAAAGCAUUGCAAAACUAUAGGCACAGUUUUUAUUUUAUCUUUCUGGCACCUGGUUUGGGCUUUGGCUUAGAUUAAAAAGACGAGCCUUCUCCUGCCCCUGCUCCCUUUUAUUCCCUGCCAUCUGCUAAGCUCGACUUUUUAUCUCUCAGGCCAAAUUUGACUCUGUAAGGGACUUUGCAUAACGUUUCAUCCUCAGAAUCGCUAAUGAUGGGCAGAGGACUGUUACAUGUGUUGGGAGGGAUUAAAGUAUAUGACCUCAGUGCCACUUAAAAAAUAAAUACUGUCUCAACUAUCA